GCUCACUUCGGGCCGGGGCGCGGGAAGGUGCGGGUUGUUGGCUGAGGCAAGCCGUGGCUCGGGCGACGCGGGGCCAGGAGGGCAGGACCGUCUGCCGGCGACAGCCCAUACCGUCUGCCGUUGCGCGACACGAACCACCCUCCGAUCCGCCAUCCCCGCGUCGUCGCCGCUAGUCCGCCCGCCCGCCCUCGGGCCCCCCGCUGCCGAGCCCGACCUCCUAAGAGCUGAAAGAAAUUAUUGAGAGUCAUAGUCCAUAGCCCCCUGCUUCGUCCCCCAACCCUCAACGACGAAAAGGACUUCGGUCCCCUGGCCCGGCGACGCCCGGGAAGGAAAGGAGAGCGACCUCCGCCCCGCGCUCAGGCCACCCUGGAGGGAGAAGCCGCCCCGCGGCCGGUAGAGCGCCCCGCCGCCGCGGAGACCCGAGUGAGUGAGUUGGGGGGCGUGCGGGCGGGGGGCCCGCCCCGAGACCCAGCCGGCCGGACUACCUCUUCCACCCCGCCCCACUCCCGCUUUGCUGGACUCUCCACGUUGCUGCCGCUCCCUCCCCGCCUGGCCAGCAUUUUCUUUCCCCAUCCAGCUUCCCUCCAGACCCCACUUUCCCCAGCUCCUCUUCUCACGCCAUCUGUGCUCCUGGGGUGCCCAAGAGCUCCUUUUUCUCCCAGUUCCAAGAGUGGCCCUCUCCUGGGUGGGGUGCAUUUCCUCCCUUCCCCGCCUCCCCCGGUUCUUUAUAUCCUAGCUACUCGCUAGAUCUUCCUUGUUCUCCAAAGAAACAUAACUCCCCCCACCGUUAAAUAAAUCCGAGGAAGGAAGGGGAUCCAGGCCUUGUUUUUCUGCUUCUUUUCCCGUGUGCAGGGAAGGGGGGUGGUAAUUGUUAAUAGACUCUAUUUCUGGCUCUGUGGAGCCUGAAGGGUGGAGGGUGGACACCCCCUUUGGCGACGGGACAGGUCAGUGGAGAUUGUCCUUGGGCCACUGAGCCAGAGUUCACCGUUUCGGCUGAGCUCUUUAUACUCUUAAGUGUUUUAAUGGAAAAUUGGGCAGAAAAAAGUACCCUUAGAGCAGUGCCAGUGAGUGGAUUCUGCUUAUCUUGGUAAGGUGCCUGCGAGGUGGGGCCCUACCCCCAAACUCCUUCCCCUCCUGUCCGGAGGAUGAACUGUGCCCUUGACCACCAGAAAUCUGGGAGGGGAAGGAGGGUGCAGAGAGGAGGCACAGCCGGCAGGCCCUCUCCCUCCCCCAGGAGAAACCAGAACCCCGCACAGCAAGCUUCAGCUUGGGGACGGGUGGAGGCCAGUCUCUGGUGCUACUCCGUAUCUAAACGGUCUUUUUCUCCUUCUUACCCACCGUACCCUGGGAAUGGGUCCUUCAUCUCUGAUUUUCCGGCAGAAAAACAAUCCUAUUGCUUUCUUGGGCUUCUACCCCCAUCCCUCCGUGAAGCAUAGGGGGAAAGAAGCUUGUGUGGGAGGAAGGAUUAAGGAGGUUUAACACCCAGCGGGGGAGCUUGCCGAGGAUCUGAGCCGCCUGGAGCCCAAGGCUGUACACGUGCCCUGUGCUGAUUCUCUGCCUAGGAAAGGACCAUGCAGCUAGAGAUCAAAGUGGCCCUGAACUUCAUCAUCUCCUACUUGUACAACAAGCUGCCCCGGCGCCGGGCAGACCUGUUUGGGGAGGAGCUAGAGCGGCUUUUGAAAAAGAAAUAUGAAGGCCACUGGUACCCUGAGAAGCCACUGAAAGGCUCUGGCUUCCGCUGUGUUCACAUUGGGGAGAUGGUGGACCCCGUGGUGGAGCUGGCCGCCAAGCGGAGUGGCCUGGCGGUGGAAGAUGUGCGGGCCAAUGUGCCUGAGGAGCUGAGUGUCUGGAUUGAUCCCUUUGAGGUGUCCUACCAGAUUGGUGAGAAGGGAGCUGUGAAAGUGCUGUACCUGGAUGACAGUGAGGGUUGCGGUGCCCCAGAGCUGGACAAGGAGAUCAAGAGCAGCUUCAACCCUGACGCCCAGGUGUUCGUGCCCAUUGGCAGCCAGGACAGCUCCCUGUCCAACUCCCCAUCGCCAUCCUUUGGCCAGUCACCCAGCCCUACCUUCAUUCCCCGCUCCGCUCAGCCCAUCACCUUCACCACCGCCUCCUUCGCUGCCACCAAAUUUGGCUCCACUAAGAUGAAGAAGGGGGGCGGGGCAGCAAGUGGUGGGGGUGUAGCCAGCAGUGGGGCGGGUGGCCAGCAGCCACCACAGCAGCCUCGCAUGGCCCGCUCACCCACCAACAGCCUGCUGAAGCACAAGAGCCUCUCUCUGUCUAUGCAUUCACUGAACUUCAUCACGGCCAACCCGGCCCCUCAGUCCCAGCUCUCACCCAAUGCCAAGGAGUUCGUGUACAACGGUGGUGGCUCACCCAGCCUCUUCUUUGAUGCGGCCGAUGGCCAGGGCAGCGGCACCCCAGGCCCGUUUGGAGGCAGUGGGGCUGGCACCUGCAACAGCAGCAGCUUUGACAUGGCCCAGGUAUUUGGAGGUGGUGCCAACAGCCUCUUCCUGGAGAAGACACCCUUUGUGGAAGGCCUCAGCUACAACCUGAACACCAUGCAGUAUCCCAGCCAGCAGUUCCAGCCCGUGGUGCUGGCCAACUGACCAUCUACCUGCCCGUGGGGCCAGGAGCACCCAAGACCACAGAAAAGAGAAAGGAAAGGCCAAAAAAAAGAGGAAAAGAAAAAUGUACAAAAAGAUUUUCGAUCUUCUCACUCUUACUUCUAGAAAAAAGAUCCAGCCCAGGCACGGAAUGGGAGGGCCCUGCAAAGCACCCAAGUGUGUUUCACUCACCCCUUACCGCUCGCCCACCGGCCUGUGAUUUAUUUGGUUGGUUUGGGUUUUAUAUUUCUUUUUCUUUUUUUUUUUUCUUACAUGUAGUUUUCUAUAUAACAUCUUUAAUGAGUGGCUUCCUGUGCUAAGAAUGGUCCAGAUGUGAACUGCUGCUCCCUGCUCCUCCCUUCCUCCUUCACACUCCUAGUUUAGGAUUGAUGUGUCCAAGCUCAUAGGGAAGAAAGAGCUGCAGCUGGAGCCUGACCCUCCCUGGAACAGGGAGAGGCUGGCCCGUGUCACUGCCUCUGUCACCCAGCUAUCCUCGCACUCAAAGCCAUCCAACCUCAGCAGGCCUUCUCGGGCCCUGCCACCUGAAUAGGUCUGACCCCAGUCCCCACUCCCUUUCAGGCUGGGCCACAGGGAGUUGCUGGCUGGCCACUUGACACCCUCCCCCUGGAGCUGAUGUCUGUGACUACAGGGAGAUUAGCACUUCGUCUAGUGAAACUCCUUUCAUCUCUGUCCUAUGGCCCCACCCCACCAUUCCCUCUAGGCCCAGACCAUCAUCAUGGCCCUGGCCAUUGAUGUGUAUGGGCUUUCUUUCCCUCAUGCAGCCCCUUCUUCCCCAGGCUGGAUGUUGUGGGUAGGGAGGGGUGUGUGUGUGUGUAUUUGGUUUGCUGUCCUUUUUUAAAGGAUUCCAAGCCAUGUGAAACUUCCCUUCUGGAUGUGAUUCUGGGUCGCAAGUCCUUAUUUAUAUGUGAGGCUGGGGAAUGGGCUGGGGGUAUUGGCAGUCCUUUUGCAGGGCAGUGUGUGUGGUGGGGUGACACCGCUGUGGCUUAGCCCAAGACACUCCCAGAGGAAAACACUGCAGAAGGAACUGGUUUGCAGACUGUGGAAGGAUCUGCAGUUUUGUUUUUGACCAAAAAAAUAAUAAUAAGUUAGCUCUGAAGGGCAGAGGGAAUACCCAAGCCCCUGAUGCCUAUGAGAAGUCCCUGGACUUCAACCCUCCUGUUGUUUGGCCUUAGCCCAGAGGGAGCUGCUCACCUGAGCACCCUUGGGGGUGGGCAGAGAGGCAGGGUGGGAUUUUAGAGUUAGUGUCUGUGCGGGGGCAGCCCUGAGCCUGGAGUUGAGACUUUGGGGUCUCUUAGUUUGGAGGUGUUGAGUGCAUUUGUGCCCCUGCCUGGUUGAGAGCUUCUUGGUACCUCUUGCCACCCCUUCUCACUGCCCUGACCCAACCCCACUGGACCUUGAUGCUGCGAGGAGUGGUGUCCUGACGGACUCAGCACUCCCGCCUGAUGUAUUGGAUCAUAGGAGAGCACUUGCUCUCCUGCCUCUGCCAGGAGAGGGCUUGUUCCUCCAACUCUAGGAGGCCAGGCAAGCAUGGACAGGAGCCAAGGGAGCAGGGUCAUUAACUUUUUCUUCUUUGCAAAGUGGGCACUUGGCAUCAGGGUCCCAAUCACCAGAAAGCACCAAAGCCCCUGGCACCCCACCCACUCCAUCCUACCCAGGGACCCCAAGUAGGCAACUGUUAUGGCAGUGGGUCCAGCCCAGGCCAGCACUGCCAGCCUCCUCUCCCUGCAGUAGGCACCAGCUCUACCUCCCCCGGCAGGCAAUGUCCUGGCUUCUCAGCCCAGCACCAUCUGUUCCCCUAGACUUCUCAGGGGCCAGCCCAGUCUGGGCCACCCUUUGUUUCCCUCAUCCUCGGCUCCCACACAGGUGACAGACCCAGCAGAUAGCUUCUCUCUGGGAAAGGUUGGAUGCUGCCUUACAUCCCCUUCUAGCCCUCCUCCCAUCCACACACACAGGCACCCACCCACACCAGGUCGGCUUGUUUCUCACAUGUAGGGAGAGAGGGGAGACCAACCCCUUUGUGUCUUUUGAAAUACGAAGAAAAAUGUGUGUUCAGGAGCAUGACUCCAGUGCUGCGCUCUUGGGCCCAGUUCAGUCUGUCUUGUCUCAAAUCUAGGCAUUUUUGCUUCAAUUUUAUUUUUUUUAAGAAUACAAAAACAGAAAUCUGCACUAAUUUACCUGGUUUCGUAGGAAAACUUUUUUUUAUUUUUUACAUUUUUUGGUGUCCGUUUGUAUUGAAUAAUUUGCUACAUUUGUAAAAUGUAAGAGGUAUAUAAUAUAUGUAUAUUUCUAACGUAAAAAACAUAAUUUUUUUCUUUUCAAGAUUUUUUCUUAAAAAGAUGAGAGAAACAUAUUUUUUCAGGAAAAACAAACUUUAAAAAAAAAAGAGGAGAAAUAAAACCUUUUCUCCCCUUUCCCCAUCCUCUAUCUAUCCCUCUUUCCCAGGAACAAAUCAAAAGGUGGAUUAUCUUCUGAAGAAUGGAAACUGUUAGUCCAGAAUGAUGUGUUUUUCUCAAUGCAGUGAGUUAUAGAUUCUCUAGUUUUCUCCCUAGGGAUGGGAAGGGGGCAUUGAGGCAAGCCUGGAGAGGAGCCCGGGGAGCAGGGUCAUGAACUUUUUUCUUUAGUGAAGGAGGAAUACAAUCAAGGGUUUUGUAUUCAGAAUGUUGUGCAAUAUUUUGGAAUGGGACAUUGGUGUGUUUAGAGAUUUUAGUUUAAAAACAAAACAAAAAGAUUGAUCAAAUCUGUACAGUUUCUAUUGUUCCAGAUUUUUUUAAGUUUGUAUUAAAAGCAUGAUACAUAAUA